AGCUUCCGGCGCCGCAGCCGAGGAGGAGGAGCCGCCCCGCAGCCUCCGCGGGGCCUAGGGGCGAAGAGUGGGGAGCCGCCCCGUCCCAGCCGCCAGGUCGACGUAGGUGGGGCCGCUGCGCCCGCCGGCGCCCCGCGGAGAUGUGGCCGGUGUCUUAGGAUUAGGUGUUGGUUGCAGGUACAAGCGGGGCGCGGCCCGGGAGACGAGGAUGGUGGGGUGGGAGUGGGGUUCUUCUGAGGACCCGGAGCGACUCGUGUUCAUUUCUGGAAUCUUCCGGUGCCUCGUGUUUGUUCUGCACAUGGAAGAUGCCCAAUAAAUUGUUUCUUUACUGGAAUGAGCUGCUGUUGUUUUAGGGGAUUGCAAGACCCCUGGGGACGGUGGCGCUGAAACCUGGACCUUGAAGAACACAGGGGCCUGCGCAAACUGAUUUGAUUUGUGGGGAAGAGAAUCACCGAGUAACCUGCCCCAACGUGACUGCUGACUCUGUGUCUACCGCGCUGCCGCGAACAGGGGGAGGAGAUGGGGAAGACUUGGUGGUAGAGAGGACAGCCUCGCAUCCAAGACGGAAUGGUGUUAAAUGCCGGCGCAAGGGCCCUUUCAGCUUGAGCCCUGUCUUUAAACCACAUGUGGGGGUCAGAGCUUUCCCUCAUUAUCAGCAUCAAUCAGCAACACAAUGAGUUCUGGAAAGUCUCCAUCCUUUUCCACAGCACUCUGCUCCAGGCCCCACUCAGGCUGCUCCAGGUUUUGUUUGUGCCUCAUGCUGAACUCCAACGUCAGGGGAAAGUAGAAGUGAGGUCGGCUGUUGCCCAGGUUUUUUGACUGGCAACCAGUUCUUGCUGCUUCUCUCAGCAGGAGAUUAAGGCGUUGUGGCCGGGUAUGGCGGGGGCGUGUGGGGAAAGGACCAGGGCUUCCACAUAUCCCAGAGACAUGCUAGGUAGGACUGUUUCUCUGUGCGGAAGCUCAUCAGAUAUUAAUAGAAUAAGUGAAAAUAAGAAUAUCCAGAAGUUAAGACAGGAACCAAAAGAACCAAAGAGGGAACCAUUCAUACUUCAAGAUCUCUAAUAAGAAGUAGCAAUAUUUAAUAUGGAAUCAAAAGCUUGGGAAUCAAAUAAUGAAGAUCUUUUAUCAAGUAGUGGUGUCACAUCUAAUGGAGGUUCUUCAAGUUCAUUUUUUGUGUCAUCUAUUCGUGGUACAAUAAUUGAAAACACAUCUUCAGCUGGGACUUUGACACAGGUUCCUUUUUUCCCUAAAUAUGAAGUGGAACUUGAUUCUCCUAGAAAAAUCAUCCCAUCUCCUGGAAAGGAACACUUUGAACGUGUUUUGGAAGAAUAUUCACAUCAAGUCAAAGAUUUACAGAGAAGACUAAAUGAAAGCAAUGAAUUGCAUGAGAAACAAAAGUUUUAUUUGAGGCAGUCAGUCAUUGAUUUGCAAACAAAACUUCAGGAGAUGCAAAUGGAGAGAGAUGCUAUGGCUGACAUCAGACGAAGGGAGAGUCAGUCCCAGGAGGAUUUAAGAAAUCAGCUUCAAAAUACAGUUCAUGAACUUGAAGCUGCCAAAUGCCUUAAAGAGGACAUGCUGAAAGACAGCAACACACAGAUAGAGCAACUACGAAAAAUGAUGCUUAGUCAUGAGGGAGUGCUUCAAGAAAUCCGGUCAAUCCUAGUUGACUUUGAAGAAGCCUCAGGCAAAAAAAUAUGUGAACAUGACAGCAUGUCUACUCUGCACUUCCGCAGCUUGGGCUCAGCUAUUAGUAAAAUACUAAGAGAAUUAGACACAGAGAUUUCUUAUCUUAAAGGGAGGAUAUUUCCAGUAGAGGAUCAACUUGAAGCACUGAAAUCUGAAUCACAGAACAAAAUAGAACUACUUCUGCAACAACACCAAGAUAGGAUUGAGCAGUUAAUAAGUGAACAUGAAGUUGAAAUAACAGGACUUACUGAGAAAGCUAGCAGUGCUCGAAGCCAAGCCAAUAGUAUCCAGAGUCAAAUGGAAAUCAUUCAAGAGCAAGCAAGAAACCAAAACUCUAUGUAUAUGCGUCAGCUCAGCGAUCUGGAAUCUACUGUUUCUCAGCUACGUUCUGAAUUAAGGGAAGCCAAAAGGAUGUAUGAAGACAAGACAGAAGAGCUGGAAAAGCAGUUAGUCCUUGCCAACUCAGAGCUAACUGAAGCCCGGACAGAGCGUGAUCAAUUCAGUCAGGAAUCUGGAAAUUUAGAUGAUCAACUUCAAAAGCUGUUGGCUGAUCUACACAAAAGGGAGAAGGAGCUGAGUCUGGAGAAGGAGCAGAAUAAGCGUCUGUGGGACCGAGACACAGGCAACAGCAUCACCAUUGACCACCUGCGGCGGGAACUGGACAACCGGAACAUGGAGGUGCAGCGCCUGGAAGCCCUGCUCAAGGCCUUGAAGAGCGAGUGUCAGGGCCAGAUGGAGCGGCAGAUGGCAGCAAUUCAAGGAAAGAAUGAAAGUCUAGAAAAAGUAUCCUCCUUGACUGCUCAGCUUGAAUCCACCAAAGAGAUGCUGCGCAAAGUAGUAGAAGAGUUGACAGCCAAGAAAAUGACUCUGGAGAGCUCAGAGAGGACAAUAUCGGACCUGACAACUUCUCUCCAGGAAAAAGAGAGAGCCAUCGAGGCUACCAAUGCAGAGAUCACAAAGCUCCGCUCCCGGGUGGACUUGAAAUUGCAGGAGCUGCAACACUUGAAAAAUGAAGGGGAUCAUCUCAGAAAUGUGCAGACAGAAUGUGAGGCCCUCAAACUGCAGAUGACAGAGAAGGACAAGGUGAUCGAGAUUCUGCGACAGCAGAUUGAGAACAUGACACAGCUGGUGGGCCAGCAUGGACGAACUGCUGGAGCUAUGCAAGUAGAAAAAGCUCAACUGGAGAAAGAAAUUAAUGAUAGGCGGAUGGAACUAAAGGAACUUAAGAUAUUAAAAGAUAAAAAAGAUGCAAAGAUCCGGGAGCUUGAGGCCAGAGUGAGUGACUUGGAGCUGGAAAAGGUGAAGCUGGUGAAUGCAGGCUCUGAGCGGCUCCGUGCAGUGAAGGACAUCAAACAAGAGAGAGAUCAAUUAUUAAAUGAGGUGAAAACAAGUAGGAGUGAAUUAAACAAUCUUUCAGAGGAGUAUGAAGUCUUAAAAAGGAAUUUCCGAAACAAAAGUGAAGAAAUGGAAAUGACUACAAAUAAGUUGAAAAUGCAAUUAAAAUCUGCACAGUCUGAACUAGAACAGACAAGAAAUACAUUAAAGUCAAUGGAAGGAUCUGAUGGUCAUGCUAUGAAAGUGGCAAUGGGGAUGCAAAAGCAAAUCACAGCCAAAAGAGGUCAGAUAGAUGCCCUUCAGAGCAAGAUACAGUUUUUGGAAGAGGCAAUGACAAAUGCAAAUAAGGAGAAACAUUUUCUGAAAGAAGAGAAAAGUAAACUCAGUCAGGAAUUGAGUACUGUUGCCACAGAAAAAAACAAGAUGGCUGGGGAGUUGGAAGUUCUGCGAUCUCAGGAACGCCGUUUGAAAGAAAAGGUUACUAAUAUGGAAGUGGCUCUGGAUAAGGCAUCUUUGCAGUUUGCAGAAUGUCAAGAUAUAAUACAGCGUCAGGAGCAAGAAUCAGUGCGCUUAAAACUUCAACACACUUUGGAUAUAAAAGAACUUCAGGGCCCUGGAUACACCUCAAAUUCUUCAUUGAAACCACGCCUUCUCCAGCCAGCAUCUGUUACUCGUUCUCAUUCUAAUGUACCAUCUUCGCAGUCUACAGCCAGCUUCCUGUCUCAUCACUCUACAAAAGCUAACACACUGAAGGAAGAUCCAACAAGGGACCUGAAACAGCUUCUCCAAGAGUUGAGAAGCGUGAUCAAUGAGGAGCCAGCUGUGUCUCUGAGCAAGACAGAGGAAGAUGGAAGAACAUCUCUGGGAGCCUUGUAUGUGGCUGUAGAGGAUAGGGUAAGAGAUUGCAUUACUGAAUCCAGCCUGAGAUCAGACAUGUGCCAUAGAAGCAACAACUCGUUGAGGGACUCCACUGAAGGAAGCAAAUCAAGUGAAACUCUUAGUAGAGAGCCAGUCACAUUACACGCAGGAGACAGGGAAGAUCCCUCUGGUUGCUUCACAUUCACAUCUGCAGCAAGUCCAUCUGUGAAAAACUCAGCUUCUCGUUCAUUCAAUUCUUCUCCUAAGAAGUCUCCAGUGCACUCACUCCUAACUAGUUCAGUUGAAGGUUCAAUAGGUUCCACAUCACAGUAUAGAUCUGCCAAACCUAUUCAUUCAUCUGAUUCUGUUAAAGAUUCACAGUCUCCGCCAAUAGAAACAACAGGAAAAACAUGCAGGAAGCUUCAGAACAGACUAGAAAGCUUGCAAACUCUGGUAGAAGAUUUACAGCUGAAGAACCAAGCAAUGUCUUCAAUGAUCAGAAAUCAAGAAAAGAGGAUACAGAAAGUAAAAGACCAGGAAAAAAUGUUACUAAAAUGACUCGUUGCUUGCCUAUUCUUUACAGAGGAAUGAGGCCCAAUUAAUUGUGGUGUUACUCGUAAUUAGUGCCCUGUGUACUUUUUCUUUUUAUGUGAAAAUUUAAUAAAAGAUACCCUGUCUUGUAAACUCUA